GAUGGAAGUAUGAUGUGAUGGAUAUAAUUAUGGGACACUGUGUGGGCACACGGCCUCCUGCUUGUUGCCUCAUCCUCCUGCUUUUCAAGCUUUUGGCCACUGUCUCCCAGGGGCUGCCAGGGACUGGACCCCUGGGCUUCCACUUCACACAUUCCAUUUAUAAUGCUACCGUGUAUGAGAACUCAGCAGCAAGGACCUACGUCAACAGCCAGAGUAGAAUGGGCAUCACCUUAAUAGAUCUAUCCUGGGAUAUCAAAUACAGAAUAGUGUCCGGAGACGAGGAAGGCUUUUUCAAAGCAGAGGAAGUCAUCAUUGCAGAUUUCUGUUUUCUCAGAAUAAGAACUAAAGGUGGCAAUUCUGCCAUAUUAAAUAGGGAAAUCCAGGAUAAUUAUUUAUUGAUAGUAAAAGGUUCUGUCAGAGGAGAGGAUUUGGAAGCAUGGACCAAAGUGAAUAUACAGGUUUUAGAUAUGAAUGAUCUGAGACCUUUGUUUUCACCCACAACAUACUCUGUUACCAUAGCAGAAAGCACACCUCUAAGGACUAGUGUUGCCCAGGUGACUGCAACAGACGCAGAUAUUGGUUCCAAUGGAGAAUUCUACUACUACUUUAAAAAUAAAGUUGAUCUCUUUUCAGUUCACCCCACGAGUGGUGUCAUCUCCUUAAGUGGUCGAUUAAAUUAUGAUGAAAAGAAUAGGUAUGAUCUGGAAAUUUUGGCUGUGGACCGGGGAAUGAAACUGUAUGGGAACAAUGGAGUGAGCAGUACUGCAAAGCUUUAUGUUCACAUUGAGCGCAUAAAUGAACAUGCCCCAACAAUCCAUGUAGUCACUCAUGUUCCUUUCUCGUUGGAAAAAGAGCCAACAUAUGCAGUGGUGACAGUUGAUGACUUAGAUGAUGGAGCGAAUGGAGAGAUCGAAUCUGUUUCCAUUGUGGCUGGGGAUCCUUUAGAUCAGUUCUUCCUGGCUAAGGAAGGAAAGUGGUUGAAUGAGUACAAGAUUAAGGAGAGGAAGCAGAUUGACUGGGAGAGCUUUCCCUAUGGCUACAAUCUCACUCUUCAAGCAAAAGACAAGGGAUCUCCUCAAAAAUGUUCAGCAUUAAAGGCAGUCUACAUUGGCAACCCCACAAGAGACACUGUCCCCAUUAGAUUUGAAAAAGAAGUGUACGAUGUGAGCAUAAGUGAAUUUUCCCCUCCUGGUGUCGUGGUUGCUAUAGUAAAAUUAAGUCCUGAACCGAUAGAUGUGGAAUACAAAUUAUCUCCUGGUGAGGAUGCAGUGUACUUUAAAAUUAAUCCUCGGUCGGGUCUGAUUGUUACAGCACGGCCACUGAAUACUGUUAAGAAGGAGGUUUAUAAACUGGAGGUGACAAACAAGGAAGGAGAUUUAAAAGCACAGGUCACCAUCAGCAUAGAAGAUGCAAAUGACCACACCCCAGAAUUUCAGCAACCACUGUAUGAUGCUUAUGUGAAUGAAAGUGUCCCAGUGGGAACCAGCGUUCUAACAGUUUCAGCUUCUGAUAAGGAUAAAGGAGAAAAUGGGUACAUCACCUAUAGUAUCGCUAGCCUGAAUUUGUUACCAUUUGUCAUUAAUCAGUUUACAGGUGUUAUUAGCACAACUGAAGAACUGGAUUUUGAAUCCUCCCCAGAAAUUUACAGAUUCAUUGUUAGAGCCUCUGACUGGGGUUCACCAUACCGCCAUGAAAGUGAGGUCAAUGUGACUAUUCGAAUAGGAAAUGUCAACGACAACAGCCCUCUCUUUGAAAAAGUGGCUUGCCAGGGAGUUAUUUCAUAUGACUUUCCAGUUGGUGGUCACAUCACAGCAGUCUCAGCGAUCGAUAUCGAUGAACUUGAACUUGUAAAGUACAAAAUCAUUUCUGGAAAUGAACUUGGCUUCUUUUAUUUAAACCCAGAUUCUGGUGUUUUACAGCUUAAAAAAUCACUGACAAAUUCUGGCAUUAAAAAUGGCAAUUUUGCCCUCAGAAUUACAGCAACUGAUGGAGAGAAUCUUGCAGACCCCAUGUCUAUUAACAUUUCAGUCCUACAUGGGAAAGUGUCUUCAAAGAGCUUCAGUUGCAGAGAAACUCGUGUGGCUCAAAAGCUGGCAGAGAAACUACUCAUUAAGGCAAAAGCAAAUGGGAAACUGAAUCUGGAAGAUGGAUUUCUUGACUUUUAUUCAAUUAAUAGACAGGGACCAUAUUUUGACAAGUCUUUUCCUUCUGAUGUGGCUGUAAAGGAGGAUCUGCCAGUUGGUGCUAACAUUCUGAAGAUUAAAGCCUAUGAUGCCGACUCUGGCUUCAAUGGAAAAGUGCUAUUUACAAUAUCAGAUGGAAAUACGGAUAGUUGCUUUAAUAUUGAUAUGGAGACUGGGCAGCUUAAAGUCCUUAUGCCCAUGGAUCGAGAACACACAGACCUCUAUCUCCUUAAUAUCACCAUCUAUGACUUAGGUAAUCCACAGAAAUCGUCAUGGAGACUGCUGACCAUCAAUGUGGAGGAUGCUAAUGACAAUAGCCCAGUUUUUAUUCAAGACAGUUACUCAGUUAACAUUCUUGAAAGUUCAGGCAUUGGUACUGAAAUCAUUCAAGUGGAAGCCAGAGACAAAGACUUAGGUUCUAAUGGUGAAGUGACUUACUCAGUCUUGACAGAUACACAGCAGUUUGCCAUCAAUAGCUCAACUGGAAUCGUUUAUGUAGCCGACCAGUUGGACCGGGAAUCCAAAGCCAAUUAUUCUUUGAAAAUAGAAGCCAGGGACAAGGCAGAGAGUGGUCAGCAGCUGUUUUCAGUUGUCACUCUUAAAGUUUUUUUAGAUGAUGUCAAUGACUGCUCCCCAGCUUUCAUUCCCAGUAGCUAUAGUGUGAAGGUUCUUGAAGAUCUCCCUGUUGGCACUGUCAUUGCUUGGCUUGAGACCCAUGAUCCAGAUCUUGGACUGGGGGGUCAAGUGCGCUAUUCUUUGGUCAAUGACUAUAAUGGGAGAUUUGAAAUAGAUAAAGCAAGUGGUGCCAUCCGCUUGAGCAAAGAGCUUGAUUAUGAGAAACAGCAGUUCUAUAACCUUACUGUGCGGGCCAAAGACAAAGGGCGGCCUGUCUCUCUGUCAUCUGUUUCCUUUGUUGAGGUGGAAGUGGUGGAUGUCAAUGAAAACCUCCACACUCCCUAUUUCCCAGACUUUGCUGUUGUUGGAUCUGUAAAGGAAAACUCACGCAUUGGAACAAGCGUGCUGCAGGUGACUGCUCGAGAUGAAGACUCCGGAAGGGAUGGAGAGAUCCAGUACUCCAUCAGGGAUGGCAGUGGUCUUGGAAGGUUCAGUAUAGACGACGAGAGUUCUUCCCGUAAGUAUGAUUCAGAAGUCAGUUUUUAUUUAUUUUUGAGACAGAAUCUUGCUCUGUUGCCCAGGCUGGGGUGCAGUGUCACAAUCUUGGCUCACUGCAGUCUCUGCCUCCUGGGUUCUAGCGAUUCUCGUGCCUCAGCCUCCCAAGUAGCUGGGAUUACAGGCGUGUACCACCACACCCAGCUAAUUUUUAUAUUUUCAGAAGAGAUGGAGUUUUGCCAUGUUUGCCAGGCUGGUCUUGAACUCCUGGCCUGAGGUGAUCCACCUGCCUCGGCCUACCAAAGUGCUGGGAUUAUAGACAUCAGCCACUGCGC